ACACCCGAGCCGCGUCCGCGAACACAGCCCAUGGCCUCCCCGCGCCUAGGGACCUUCUGCUGCCCCACGCGGGACGCAGCCACGCAGCUCGUGCUGAGCUUCCAGCCGCGGGCCUUCCACGCGCUCUGCCUGGGCAGCGGCGGGCUCCGCUUGGCGCUGGGCCUUCUGCAGCUGCUGCCCGGCCGCCGGCCCGCGGGCCCCGGGUCCCCCGCGACGUCCCCGCCGGCCUCGGUCCGCAUCCUGCGCGCUGCCGCUGCCUGCGACCUUCUCGGCUGCCUGGGUAUGGUGAUCCGGUCCACCGUGUGGUUAGGAUUCCCAAAUUUUGUUGACAGCGUCUCGGAUAUGAACCACACGGAAAUUUGGCCUGCUGCUUUCUGCGUGGGGAGUGCGAUGUGGAUCCAGCUGUUGUACAGUGCCUGCUUCUGGUGGCUGUUUUGCUAUGCAGUGGAUGCUUAUCUGGUGAUCCGGAGAUCGGCAGGACUGAGCACCAUCCUGCUGUAUCACAUCAUGGCGUGGGGCCUGGCCACCCUGCUCUGUGUGGAGGGAGCCGCCAUGCUCUACUACCCUUCCGUGUCCAGGUGUGAGCGGGGCCUGGACCACGCCAUCCCCCACUAUGUCACCAUGUACCUGCCCCUGCUGCUGGUUCUCGUGGCGAACCCCAUCCUGUUCCAAAAGACAGUGACUGCAGUGGCCUCUUUACUUAAAGGAAGACAAGGCAUUUACACGGAGAACGAGAGGAGGAUGGGAGCCGUGAUCAAGAUCCGAUUUUUCAAAAUCAUGCUGGUUUUAAUUAUUUGUUGGUUGUCGAAUAUCAUCAAUGAAAGCCUUUUAUUCUAUCUUGAGAUGCAAACAGAUAUCAAUGGAGGUUCUUUGAAACCUGUCAGAACUGCAGCCAAGACCACAUGGUUUAUUAUGGGAAUCCUGAAUCCAGCCCAGGGAUUUCUCUUGUCUUUGGCCUUCUACGGCUGGACAGGAUGCAGCCUGGGUUUUCAGUCUCCCAGGAAGGAGAUCCAGUGGGAAUCACUGACCACCUCGGCUGCUGAGGGGGCUCACCCAUCCCCACUGAUGCCCCAUGAAAACCCUGCUUCCGGGAAGGUGUCUCAAGUGGGUGGGCAGACUUCUGACGAAGCCCUGAGCAUGCUGUCUGAAGAUGAGAUGAAUGCUAGGACUUUGACCAAAGUUGGUCCAUGAAAAACUCCAUGCACUGAAUACUGAGCAUUUUCUGAAGCUGAUGACAAACCUGCUAGGACACAGACACAGUCAGUCUUUUGUCUUUUCCUCUCCAGGUUCUGAUGCCAGCACAAUUGAAAUUCACACUGCAAGUGAAUCCUGCAACAAAAAUGAGGGUGACCCUGCUCUCCCAACCCAUGGAGACCUAUGAAGGGGAUGUGCUGGGGGUCCAGACCCCAUAUUCCUCAGACUCAACAAUUCUUGUUCUUUAGAACUGUGUUCUCACCUUCCCAACACUGCACUGCCGAAGUGUAGCGGCCCCCAAACCUUGCUCUCAUCACCAGCUAGAGCUUCUUCCCGAAGGGCCUUUAGGAUAGGAGAAAGGGUUCAUGCACACACGUGUGAGAAUGGAAGAGCCCCCUCCAGACCACUCUACAGCUGCUCUAGCCUUAGUUGCCACUAGGAAGUUUUCUGAGGCUGGCUGUAAAGUAAGUGUAAGGUCCACAUCCUUGGGGAAGUAGUUAAAUAAAAUAGUUAUGACUGA